ACAGGCCAGGUCGUCAACUCAACUGUCAAGGUGUCCAUUGUACCAGCUGGGCCAUGGAUCCCUCCCGCCUGAAAUCUGACUCCACCUGCCAAGAGUCUGAGCCUGCAGGCCUAGAUUUCGACUCUGCUGGCCAAGAUUAUUUCUCUGCAGCCCAAUAAUUCGACUCUUUCUACCAAGAAUUGGACCUGGACUCUCUUAACGAAGAUCUUCUUUCCCAGUCCAUGCCACAUGCCAGGACAGAGACCUCUGUGGGCACAUAUGAAUCCCACUCGACUUCUGAACUGGAGGAUCUGACAGAGCCCGAGCAAAGAGAGCUCAAAACCAAACUCACUAAAUUGGAGGCUGAAAUUGUAACCCUACGCCACGUACUAGCAGCCAAAGAGAGACGCUGUGGGGAACUCAAGAGGAAGUUAGGCCUCACCGCCUUGGUAGGGCUGAGACAGAAUCUGUCCAAGAGCUGGCUUGAUGUUCAGGUCUCCAACACCUAUGUGAAACAGAAGACAUCAGCUGCUCUGUCCACCAUGGGCACUCUCAUCUGCAGGAAGCUUGGAGGCGUGAAGAAGUCGGCCACAUUCAGAUCUUUUGAAGGUCUGAUGGGGACAAUCAAGUCCAAAGUCUCAGGGGGCAAAAGAGCUUGGCCCUGACUGUCUUUCUUCUGCGGAGGGUGGGGUUGAUCUGCUCUCAGUUUUGGGGUGUGGGGAAGACCCACUCCAGAUUCCGGGGAGUGGGAAUGAGCCACUCCCAGUUCUGGAGAGUGAGGAUGACCAUCUCCACUUUCUGGAACCAGAAUGAGCCCCCUUGGUAACCUUGCCUGGUACUAAACCAGUGCAAGGACCCCCUUCCCUUAUUACAUUUGCAACUCUGCCCAACAAAAACAAGCAAGCAAACCACAAUGGUAAAGUGGUUAAUUCAGGAAAUUGACAGAAUCCAGUUUUGAGAAAAGAACACAGAUAUUUGCUGCUUUUAAGAUAGAGAACCCAAAGUUUUGUACCUGGUUAUUUUUCACUUAAGUUUGUAGACGAAAUGUGCCAUUAUAUUAGCUUUCCUGAGACUGUAUCUAAUGGGCAAGUCAGUGGCUCCAGAGGGGUCUUAGGCCAAAGCCCAAACUCUCUUUUGGAAAACUAGCUUAUUAGAAAGCCAAAGUAGAGUUCUGUUUAAGCUUGAAAGAGGUAUGAAGUAAUCUGUAGUGUUUUUUUGGUUUGUUUGUUUGUUUUCCCUUCCCCAUUUCCUUCCUUCCCUCAGUCUCAAAGUCACCUUGAAAGCUUCACCUGGCCUACAACUUUUAUUUUAAAAAGAUGAUCAAGAAAACUUCAUCUUCUCUGAGACUCAGAAAAAGAGGGGAAAAUAGUGGUAGUGCACUAAUUGUUACAUUACUAAUAUAGCUUUUGUAAAACUCGUUUGUUUUCAAAGGUCUGGACUAAGCAAAACAACAGUGUCAGUUUAGGAAAUUAUUACUACUUUGAACACAAACUGAAAUUGCAACUUUGCCUUGUGCUUUGUUUAUAAUUUCUUUAUAUAUCAAAAUGAGUGUUUUAAAGUUUAACCCUUGAAGCAGCAUGUCUUUGCCAUAGCAGCACUUCACUUAAAAGGAAGAAAUUGCCUCUCUGGCAGCAAUUCCUAGUUAGUUACCACCUCCAGCUGAGGGGCUGGAGGAAAACAGGUAUAGCCAAAUUCAAGAAAGAUAAACCCCUGUCUCAAGGAACAUUUUAAAAAGAACGUCUGUCCCCUGUGAUGCUGGCUGUUAUGCCUUUGAAUGGACCUAACUAUACAUCUUUGCUCUUAACUCCAAGUCUGCCCUUCUUUUUAGGAAACCCUAAAGGAGAAGGAAGCAGAAUAUAACCCUCUGGAGAGCUCAAGACAGUAGGAACCUGGACGGUGCUUGUUUGAAUUUUCUGAUAUCUGAUUUUCACACGAAUAUACUUUUUGUUUGUUUUCCUUUUCCAUUUUCAAAAUGCCAAGAUCUGGGAGCCUCUUUCACUCCUCUAGACACACUGCCUGAGAUAGAAGUUUGCAUCUUAUUGGCUGUGGGCAGAGACUAGGACCCUUAUGGGUACAUUUCAGUAAUCUCUCACUGCCUAAAAUGGUAAUCCCUCCAGCCUAAGAGGAUGAUUCUGUUUUGUUGACUCUUGAAUGCUCCCCCAACAUUCCUUUGGUUUUCCUAUAAGCAAAACCAAAUACCACUAUAAAUACAAAAGCAUCUGGUAAACUGUAAAGUUACUCAUGUAUCCCAACCCUCCACAGAUUUCUGAAGACAAAGUUUUGCUUGGAUUAAAACAAGAUGUUUUACUAUUUUGCAUGUUCGAUUUUUAAUUUGUUGUGUUUAUCAACCAAAAUGGCUUUGUAUGCUGGAGAACAAGAGGUGAGCCUGCAGCAUACAAGAAAUGAAAGUAGUCCAACAGGCAAAGGCUUUGACAUAUUUCAGGAAGGCUUGUGUUAGGGACAAUCUCAGACUAUUAUCAUGGGCCAAACCUGAGAGAUGUUAUAUUUUAUUUAAUAAUUUCUACAACAGUAGUAAGUUUCCCCAAUAAAUUCUCAACUCCGUAAAA